GAGAAGCGGCACACUCGGCGAGAGGGGUUGAGAUUGUUUUAUUCCACUCCAGGUGUUGCUGUCCUCUUGGGUUCCACUUCGGAUUUUGAACCCCUGUAUUUUCUUUUCAAAACCCCCUUUUCCAGUGGAAAUGCUCUGUUGUUAAAAAGGAAGAAACUGUCUUUCUGAAACUGACAUCACGAUGCUCCCAGAUUUUAUGCUGGUUCUCAUCGUCCUUGGCAUCCCUUCCUCAGACGGAAAGUGCACCUUCUGACAGUGGUAACACAGGUGGAGAUGUAUGCUGUGCGUGAAAGAGCAGAGCUGCUUGCUGCCCCUGGAUCUUGGUGAGGAGCAGGAUUCCUGUACCUUCACAGGGAGCACAGCUGCCCACCACAGGUUUCAACUCAAUCGCCGAAAAUGAAGAUGCCCUCCUCAGACAUUUGUUCCAAGGUUAUCAGAAAUGGGUCCGCCCUGUAUUACAUUCUAAUGACACCAUAAAAGUAUAUUUUGGAUUGAAAAUAUCCCAGCUUGUAGAUGUGGAUGAAAAGAAUCAGCUGAUGACAACCAAUGUGUGGCUCAAACAGGAAUGGACAGACCACAAGUUACGCUGGAAUCCUGAUGAUUAUGGUGGGAUCCAUUCCAUUAAAGUUCCAUCAGAAUCUCUGUGGCUUCCUGACAUAGUUCUCUUUGAAAAUGCUGACGGCCGCUUCGAAGGCUCCCUGAUGACCAAGGUCAUCGUGAAAUCAAACGGAACUGUUGUCUGGACCCCUCCCGCCAGCUACAAAAGCUCCUGCACCAUGGACGUCACGUUUUUCCCGUUCGACCGACAGAACUGCUCCAUGAAGUUUGGAUCCUGGACUUAUGAUGGCACCAUGGUUGACCUCAUUUUGAUCAAUGAAAAUGUCGACAGAAAAGACUUCUUCGAUAACGGAGAAUGGGAAAUACUGAACGCAAAGGGGAUGAAGGGGAACAGAAGGGACGGCGUGUACUCCUAUCCCUUUAUCACGUAUUCCUUCGUCCUGAGACGCCUGCCUUUAUUCUAUACCCUCUUUCUCAUCAUCCCCUGCCUGGGGCUGUCUUUCCUAACAGUUCUUGUGUUCUAUUUACCUUCGGAUGAAGGAGAAAAACUUUCAUUAUCCACAUCGGUCUUGGUUUCUCUGACAGUUUUCCUUUUAGUGAUUGAAGAAAUCAUCCCAUCGUCUUCCAAAGUCAUUCCUCUCAUUGGAGAGUACCUGCUGUUCAUCAUGAUUUUUGUGACCCUGUCCAUCAUUGUUACCGUGUUUGUCAUUAACGUUCACCACAGAUCUUCUUCCACGUACCACCCCAUGGCCCCCUGGGUUAAGAGGCUCUUUCUGCAGAAACUUCCAAAAUUACUUUGCAUGAAAGAUCAUGUGGAUCGCUACUCAUCCCCAGAGAAAGAGGAGAGUCAACCAGUAGUGAAAGGCAAAGUCCUCGAAAAAAAGAAACAGAAACAGCUUAGUGAUGGAGAAAAAGUUCUAGUUGCUUUUUUGGAAAAAGCUGCUGAUUCCAUUAGAUACAUUUCGAGACAUGUGAAGAAAGAACAUUUUAUCAGCCAGGUAGUACAAGACUGGAAAUUUGUAGCUCAAGUUCUUGACCGAAUCUUCCUGUGGCUCUUUCUGAUAGUGUCAGUAACAGGCUCGGUUCUGAUUUUUACCCCUGCUUUGAAGAUGUGGCUACAUAGUUACCAUUAGGAAUUUAAAAGACAUAAGACUAAAUUACACCUUAGACCUGACAUCUGGCUAUCACACAGACAGAAUCCAAAUGCAUGUGCUUGUUCUACGAACCCCGAAUGCGUUGUCUUUGUGGAAAUGGAACAUCUCCUCAUGGGAGAAACUCUGGUAAAUGUGCUCAUUUGUGGUUGCCAUGAGAGUGAGCUGCUUUUAAAGAAAGUGGAGCCUCCUCAGACCCCUGCCUUGGCUUUCCCAGACAUUCAGGGAGGGAUCAUAGGUCCAGGCUUGAGCUCACAUGUGGCCAGAGUGCACAAAAAGCUGUUGCUACUUGGUGGAGGAACACCUCCUAGAAGCAGCAGGCCUCGGUGGUGGGGGAGGGGGGAUUCACCUGGAAUUAAGGAAGUCUCGGUGUCGAGCUAUCUGUGUGGGCAGAGCCUGGAUCUCCCACCCUGCACUGGCCUCCUUGGUGGUUUUGUCUGAGCUGCAAACUGGGGCCGUGUUAUGCUUGUUAGCAAUGGGCCAGGCAAAUCUCAACAAGGGUUUGGGGAUUACACUGGCAGGAUAGCUGGCACUGCACACUUAACAAUAACACAGAUUCCAAGUUGCCUGGCCUACCGAAGCAGGUGUUAUUCAUGGUUUAUUCCCAGCAUGAUAAGGCUUUCAGAUGGUGAAACUGGAGCCCACUGUGAGCUGUGACUUCCUUUAAGGUCAUGCAUACCAAAAUAACUCACAAUAGAAACAAAGCCCUUUGCUACCAGAAGUGGAUUCAUUAAUACCCAUUAUCUUUUCCUAGUAAACUAGUGUACAGAA